AUGCACCGUUUCUUUGUCAAGCAGGAGGAUAUAGCUUCAGACCCAAUAGGAGAACCCGCGCAGACCGGGGGGAGGUUUGGGGAAGGCCUGGGCAAAGAAGCGCGGGGGAUUCAUUACCCGCUGGGUUCUCCUCGGCAGCGCGUCUCCCUCCGGGAGCAGGCAACGGAGCCUCCCAAGUCCAGAGCAGAGAACCUGACCCGGCGGGAUCCCGGGCUUAUAUCAGCUGAGUUCCGUGACACCUCCCGGGGCGGGACAUCGCGCAGGAGACAGACAGAGGUACAGCCCAAUCGCAUCGUUACGUGGAGCCGGAAGCCCACUCUUGCAACUACAACAGUCUUGAUUUUCAGUUCUUAUUUCACCCAGGGAAGGAGACCUGGGUAUCCACCCCAUGUCCUCCAGAGAACUUCCCUGGCCCCGCUCGGAGUCUUCCUGGGACGCCACAGGCUCGGAGAGCGCUCCGCAGGUUUCUCCCCCGGCGCCUCCAAAUCUUUCGAUUCCUACUCGAAUUACUCCGUCAGCUGCUGGAAGAGGGGCAAGGGAGCCAGGAGGACUUCUGGAGCCCGCCCAGCAAGACCCUCUCUCUCCCAUCUUCUGCUCAAGGGCUCGAGGUCUCAGUGGACAGAGCUGAAGAAAAGCCGUCUAUGGAGCCUGCGCCAGGCGCAGACUGGGUCGUCGCAGUCUGGGUCGUCGCAGUCUGGGCCGGGGCGCUGGAAGUCUUACUCACUUCUCAAGAACCCGCAAGGGAUCAGGCCUGACCCUUUGCAAGUGACAGAAUCCAAAGCUUUGAGCUCAUGGGAAAGUGGCUGGAAAGAAGGUCACUGUAGGGCCGCACAGGUCUCUGGCGAGGCUACCCAAGAACAUUUAAAUCCCUGCCCAGAGAAGAAGAGGCUCCAGCUGUCCUGCACCUUCCUGGGAACUGGCAGUCCCUCCGCGCAGGGGUUCUGCAGCGACCGGCAGCGCGAGGAGACAAGGAUGGUGGCCAGUUAACAGAAAAUCAAGGCAGCGGGAAAGGUCUGGAAAACACCACCUACUAUCACCUCUGGAGCCUGGGAUUAUGGGAUAAGUUUUCGAUUUUUAAAUGUAUUGUCAAAUAGCUAAAGUACACGGAAAGUGCGAAAUAAUAGUAAAUUGAACACCUGUGUAUUCACCACACAGCUUAAGCAAUAACAUUAGCAAUAUUUGGGUACCCAGCUGGUCUCAUUCCCUCAUUCCACUUGUCCCCUACUCACCUGAUAGCCAGUACAAUUUUAUGAAUUUAAAGUUACUAAUUCCCAUGCAACUGUUUAUACUUUUAGUAAAUGUGUUUAUGUCCCUCAUCAACACAUGACACUGAUUCAACACAUGUAUAUGCGUUUAAGCUGCAUGUAAAUGGCAUCAUGUUGGCCAGGUGCAGUUACUCACGACUGUAAUUCCAGCACUUUGGAAGGCUGAGAGGGAAGACGGCUUGAGGCCCAGAGUUUGAGACCAGCCUGGGCAACAUAGCAAGACCCUAUCUCUAAAAAAAAAAAAUUGUUUGUUUGUUUGUUUGUUUGUUUGAGACGGAGUCUUGCUGUGUCACUCAGGCUGGAGUGCAGUGGCGCAAUCUCGGCUUGCUGCAAUGUCGGCCUCCGGGGUUCAAGCAAUUCUCCUGCCUUGGCCUCCCAAGUAGCUGGGACUACAGGCACAUCCCACCACGCCCAGCUGAUUUUUGUAUUUUUAGUAGAGACAAGGUUUCACCAUAUUGGCCAUGCUGGUCUACGAACUCUUGACCUCAUGAUCUGCCUGCCUCGGCUUUCCAAAGUGCUGGAAUUACAGGUGUGAGCCCCCGCGCCCAGCCAAAAAAAUUGUUUUAAAUUAGCUGGGUGUGGUGGUGCCUGCCUAUGAAGUCCCAGCUACUCAGGAGGCUGAAGUGGGAAGAUGGCUUGAGCCCAGGAGUUGAAGGAUGCUAUGAGCUCUGAUUGUGCCACUGCACCCCUGCAUGGGCAAUAGAGUGAGACCCUGUCUCUUUAAAAAAAAAAAAAAAAGUAUCAUAUUGUAUGUGUUCUGUAGAACUUGCUCCCACACUUUAACAUUUUGCUUUAAAGAUUUGUUCAUGUACUUAGAUCAUUCCUUUUCACUGCUUUAUGAGCUGAAUCAUUUCUGCUCUUCUUUCCAUCCAUACCCAUUGGUCUCCAAAGUAUCCAGGCCUCCCCAAAAGUUCCUGCAGGAGACCUCAGUUCCACUGGCUUUCAGGUCAUUAUUGUUCCAGCACUACUUCUCCAUUUCUGGUUCCAGCCCUUCUCUCCCACAUUCUCAAGCUUCUAGAGGGUCAUAAGAGAGGAAAAACGCCAAAUGCCUUUGAUAAAAUGUUGCCUUUCCAGUGGUAUGCAUGUUUGUGUGGAGUGGGAGGGAAGUGAGGGCAGAUGUGACUUACUCUCAGCAUUAAUUCAAGUUUAAAAGUAAAAUCUUUAGGUUUGCCUUGUCCAGUAAAAAAUGCCAAGAGCCAUAA